AGACUGUAUCAAGCAAAUCUAUAGACAUGUCUGUGGAAAAGAUGACAAAAGUAGAAGAGAGUUUUCAAAAGGCCAUGGGACUUAAGAAGACGGUCGACAGGUGGCGAAAUUCACAUACUCACUGUCUGUGGCAAAUGGCAUUGGGCCAGAGAAGAAACCCGUAUGCCACCCUAAGGAUGCAGGACACCAUGGUACAGGAAUUGGCACUGGCCAAAAAGCAACUACUAAUGGUCCGUCAAGCUGCCCUGCACCAGCUGUUUGAAAAGGAGCAUCAGCAGUACCAGCAGGAACUAAAUCAGAUGGGCAAAGCUUUUUAUGUAGAGAGAUUCUGAUGGCAUCCAAAACACUGCUCUUCCAUUCUCAACAUGCCUGCUAACCUAGCCUUCUAGAACCUCUACCACCUUGAACCUCCUUCCCAAAACAUACCUGGAUCUUGCUAUCUGUCAGGGACUUAAGACAGCACUUCCACUCUCACUUCUCCACUCUCUCGUUAAUCCUUUGCCGCUAUUUGGGAAACAAUCUAUGAAACAACAGUAACAACAAGAGUGACGCCUUGUGGUCAUAGUGGGAUUUACUAUGUUGAUGUAAGGGGGCAGGGGUGGGGAGGGGUGGACAAUGAGAGUUGAGAAUCCUGAUUUGGUAUAACAAAUAAAUUUACUUCCUAAAGGCUCAAA